AGGCGCCCGCGGGGCUGUCCGCGGUCGCGCCGGGCUCCGCCUGCAGUGUGGCCCGUCCGGACAGUCCCUCACCCCGGCCUGCGCUGCUGCGUGGACUCGGGCCUCAGGAAUUCCGCUGCGGCCCAAGGCUUGCCGUUUGACGAGGAGCAGUCGCGGUAGGCGGUGGGCAAGGCUGCCCUGGGCGGAGGCCGAGGCGCGGCUCGGACUCCAGCAUGGCGACCGCGGUGCGCGCUGUGGGCUGCCUCCCCGUGCUGUGUAGCGGGACGGCAGGUGAGAGCUGGGACGCCGGGAGCAGGGGCUCUGAGCGGGCCGGGAGUGGGGGGCUCGCCUGGGGCCUGCAGAAGUCGGGGCGGAGGGAAGCGAGAAGCCGCGGCCCCCGGCUCUUCACGCCGUGCCCCCACCUUCCGCCGGAGCCGCUGUGUGACCUUGCGCGCGUCCUCUCCCUCUCUGGGUCGCGGAGCUCUUGUCUGUAAAAUGAGGGGGAACUGGACGUCGUUCUUCAGGGUUCUUCCCAGUUCACGAAACCGCUUGAGCGUGCUUGGCGAAGAGGAGCGGAAACUGGUCAUUUAUUGGGGAGGCAGUGUUCCCUAAACACCUUACCAGCAGCUUCCAUUUUGGCAUGGAAGAGUGUUCUCGGCAAUGGCCAUUUGUCAUCACUGGGAACCAGAGACACCCAUCCCUACGCCAGCUUGAGCCGUGCACUGCAGACACAAUGCUGUAUUUCUUCUCCCAGUCACCUGAUGAGCCAGCAGUAUAGACCAUAUAGUUUCUUCACUAAAUUGACUGCAGAUGAGCUGUGGAAAGGCGCUUUAGCAGAGACUGGUGCUGGAGCAAAAAAAGGAAGAGGCAAAAGAACUAAAAAGAAGAAAAGAAAGGAUCUGAACAGGGGUCAGAUCAUUGGUGAAGGGCGUUAUGGUUUUCUAUGGCCCGGACUGAAUGUCCCUCUUAUGAAAAAUGGAGCAGUGCAGACCAUUGCCCAAAGAAGCAAGGAAGAGCAGGAGAAGGUGGAGGCAGACAUGAUCCAGCAGAGAGAAGAGUGGGACCGAAAGAAGAAGAUGAAGGUUAAACGGGAGCGAGGAUGGAGUGGAAACUCAUGGGGAGGCAUCAGUCUUGGCCCCCCUGACCCUGGUCCCUGUGGAGAAACAUAUGAGGAUUUUGAUACCAGGAUACUUGAGGUAAGAAACGUUUUCACUAUGACUGCGAAAGAGGGAAGAAAGAAAUCGAUCCGUGUCUUGGUGGCUGUGGGGAACGGAAAAGGAGCUGCAGGUUUUUCUAUUGGGAAAGCUACUGAUCGGAUGGAUGCUUUCAGGAAAGCAAAGAACAGAGCAGUUCACCAUUUGCAUUAUAUAGAACGAUAUGAAGACCAUACAAUAUUCCAUGAUAUUUCAUUAAGAUUUAAAAGGACGCAUAUCAAGAUGAAGAAACAACCCAAAGGUUACGGCCUCCGCUGCCACAGGGCCAUCAUCACCAUCUGCCGGCUCAUUGGCAUCAAAGACAUGUAUGCCAAGGUCUCUGGGUCCAUUAAUAUGCUCAGCCUCACCCAGGGCCUCUUCCGUGGGCUCUCCAGACAGGAAACCCAUCAACAGCUGGCUGAUAAGAAGGGCCUCCAUGUUGUGGAAAUCCGGGAGGAAUGUGGCCCUCUGCCCAUUGUGGUUGCGUCCCCCCGGGGGCCCUUGAGGAAGGAUCCAGAGCCAGAAGAUGAGGUUCCAGACGUCAAACUGGACUGGGAAGAUGUGAAGACUGCACAGGGAAUGAAGCGCUCUGUGUGGUCUAAUUUGAAGAGAGCCGCCACGUAACCUCUCUGGCCUUGUGCAGCCAGUUCCUGUGCUGCCCUGCACCUAGGAGAGACUCAGCCCCUCACAGCUUGGGAUGUUACCUUGCCUUUUGUUUGUUUUGAGGGAAGUUUAAUCUUUAAACUCUUUGGAAAUAAAUAAUUAUAGCUUUCAUUUGUUGAGCACAUGUUAUAUGCCAAUGUGAUAGAACCUUUACAUACAUAUCUCAGUUCAAGACUACUUUAAAUAUUCAUCCAAAGUAACAAAAGUAAAUGAAUUAGGGAGACGGGGUUAAUAAUUUGACCCAAUCAGUAAUAAUGUACACAAUGAUAAUUGCUGUAGUAAUUAUAGCUAAUAUAUAUGAACUCAUUCAUCCAAAGUGAAUGUGAUUAACUUCAUUUUACAGAGCAGUUAAGUAACUUGACUACCGUGAGGAACUUCCAAACCGUUUUCCACAGUGGAAAUGGAAGUUGUAGGCUACUAUUGGGAAUGUUAAAUGGUAUAUUAAUUGUAUACCAUUGCAAUUUUGACUUGUAUUUCCCUGAUGGCUGAUGAUGUUGAACAUCUUUUCAUGUGCUGAUUGGCCAUUUGUAUAUGUUUUUUGGAGAAAUGUCUAUUCAGAGCCUUUGCCCAUUUAAAAAGUUAUUUUUUAUUAUUAUUGAGUUCCUUAUAGUUUCUAGAUAUAAGCCCCCCUAUCAUACAUGCUUUACAGAAGUUUUUACCCAUUCUGUGGAAUAUAUAUAUUUUUAUUUCUUUGCAUACUCUUUCUGCCCCACCCACAUCCUCUUUCUGGGACACUGAUGACCAAAAUGUUGAAUCUUUUACUAUUGUCCCGUGAGUCCCUGAGGCGCUGUUUAUUUUUUUUCCAGUCUGUUUUCUCUGUGUUGCUCAGUUUAGGUAAUUUCUAUUGUUUUAUCUUCAGAAUAACUGGUUAUUUACUCUUUCCUUUCCAUUCUGCUCUUGAACCAUCCAUGCAGUACUUUAACUUUGACUGUCAUUGUAUAUUUCAGUUAAAAUUUCCAUUUGGUUUAUUUUUUAUGUCUUCUCUUUAUUUGCUGAGGCUAUUUGCUGAGACUUUUUUUUUCUUUAAAUGGCUUCAAGAGUGUUUAUAAUUGCUCACUGAAGCAUUUUUAUGGUGGCUGCUUUAAAAUCUUUGUCAUCAGGUAGGUGUGGUGGCUCACGCCUAUAACCCCAGCACUUUGUGAAGGUGAGGCAGGAGGAUUGCUUCAGCCCAGGAGUUUGAGAUCAGCCUAGGCAACAAAGUGAGACCUCAUCUCUACAAAAAGUAAAAGUAAAUUUAAAAGUUAGACACACAUGGUGGUGUAUGCCUGUAGUCCCAGCUACAUAGGAGGCUGAAGUGGGAGGAUCAUUUGAUUGCAGGAGGUUGAGGCUGCAGUGAGCCUUGUUCAUGCCACUCCAGCCUGGGUGGCAGAGUGAGACCUUGUCUCCAAAAAAAAAAAAAAAAUUGUCAUAAAGUUUCAACAUCUGUGUCAUCUUAGUGUUGACAUCCCUUGAGGUUUUUUCUCAUUCAAGUUUACAAUGUCCUAGUUCUUGUUAUGAUGAGUGACUUUGGCUGUAUCCUGGUCAUCUUCACUGUUAUGAAGCUCUGGGAGUUAUUUAAAUCUCUCAGCAUGCUUCCUCUGACGGUGCUGGUAUGGGAUGGGGCACUGCCUCGUUACUGCCUGGUGAGGAUGGAGAUCCAGGUUUCCUCCUGUCGCUGUCCUCGGGACCUCUGCUGAGGCCUUUCUGCUGGAAGUAGGAGGAGCACCCUAAUGGCACCGUGGGAUAGGGAGCAGGCCAUGUUAGGCUGGAUGGUGAAAGUUUUCAGCCUGUGACGUUGUCUGGUGUGGGUGGGUCCCCUUUUUUUGUGUGUGGUAUUUUGCUAGAGUAAGGUAGUUAUUUCCUAAAACUUAUCUGUCCUGUUAGUUUUCCUUCUUAAGUACCUAACAAAUAUAAAGACAAUGAACUUUAAGCAAUAAAAGACAAUGAUCCUUUGGAGAGGGGAAACAAAA